ACGGCGUCUGGGAGGGACCCAGGAGCAGUCGGGGGGUUUGAGAGUGGCGGCGGCCGCGGAGGGCCUGGCAGGCCCCGCCGCUGCAAGGAACGCCCCGAACGCGCGCGCCCGGCGUGUAGCGGCCCCAAGACCCGCGCCGCCGCUGCCGCGUGCGGGGGCGGGGAGGGCGGGGCGCCAGGAGCCGCGGCGGCGGGAGAUGCGGGCGGCUGCGGGCACCCGGCGGGCUCGGCUUGGCCGCCGCCGCCUUCUACGGCUCCGCCGCGGGGGUCGCAGCGGCUGCCGCGCCGUCCUCGAGUUUCCAGCGUGAGGAGGAGGCUGAGGGCGGAGAGGCGCAUCGUGUUCGAGGCGGAGACCGAGGGGGAGCCCCGCGCGCGGCGUCGCUCAUUGCUAUGGACAGUGCUAUCACCCUGUGGCAGUUCCUUCUUCAGCUCCUGCAGAAGCCUCAGAACAAGCACAUGAUCUGUUGGACCUCUAAUGAUGGGCAGUUUAAGCUUUUGCAGGCAGAAGAGGUGGCUCGUCUCUGGGGGAUUCGCAAGAACAAGCCUAACAUGAAUUAUGACAAACUCAGCCGAGCCCUCAGAUACUAUUAUGUAAAGAAUAUCAUCAAAAAAGUGAAUGGUCAGAAGUUUGUGUACAAGUUUGUCUCUUAUCCAGAGAUUUUGAACAUGGAUCCAAUGACAGUGGGCAGGAUUGAGGGUGACUGUGAAAGUUUAAACUUCAGUGAAGUCAGCAGCAGUUCCAAAGAUGUGGAGAAUGGAGGGAAAGAUAAACCACCUCAGCCUGGUGCCAAGACCUCUAGCCGCAAUGACUACAUACACUCUGGCUUAUAUUCUUCAUUUACUCUCAACUCUUUGAACUCCUCCAAUGUAAAGCUUUUCAAAUUGAUAAAGACUGAGAAUCCAGCCGAGAAACUGGCAGAGAAAAAAUCUCCUCAGGAGCCCACACCAUCUGUCAUCAAAUUUGUCACGACACCUUCCAAAAAGCCACCGGUUGAACCUGUUGCUGCCACCAUUUCAAUUGGCCCAAGUAUUUCUCCAUCUUCAGAAGAAACUAUCCAAGCUUUGGAGACAUUGGUUUCCCCAAAACUGCCUUCCCUGGAAGCCCCAACCUCUGCCUCUAACGUAAUGACUGCUUUUGCCACCACACCACCCAUUUCGUCCAUACCCCCUUUGCAGGAACCUCCCAGAACACCUUCACCACCACUGAGUUCUCACCCAGACAUCGACACAGACAUUGAUUCAGUGGCUUCUCAGCCAAUGGAACUUCCAGAGAAUUUGUCACUGGAGCCUAAAGACCAGGAUUCAGUCUUGCUAGAAAAGGACAAAGUAAAUAAUUCAUCAAGAUCCAAGAAACCCAAAGGGUUAGAACUGGCACCCACCCUUGUGAUCACGAGCAGUGAUCCAAGCCCACUGGGAAUACUGAGCCCAUCUCUCCCUACAGCUUCUCUUACACCAGCAUUUUUUUCACAGACACCCAUCAUACUGACUCCAAGCCCCUUGCUCUCCAGUAUCCACUUCUGGAGUACUCUCAGUCCUGUUGCUCCCCUAAGUCCAGCCAGACUGCAAGGUGCUAACACACUUUUCCAGUUUCCUUCUGUACUGAACAGUCAUGGGCCAUUCACUCUGUCUGGGCUGGAUGGACCUUCCACCCCUGGCCCAUUUUCCCCAGACCUACAGAAGACAUAACCUAUGCACUUGUGGAAUGAGAGAACCGAGGAACGAAGAAACAGACAUUCAACAUGAUUGCAUUUGAAGUGAGCAAUUGAUAGUUCUACAAUGCUGAUAAUAGACUAUUGUGAUUUUUGCCAUUCCCCAUUGAAAACAUCUUUUUAGGAUUCUCUUUGAAUAGGACUCAAGUUGGACUAUAUGUAUAAAAAUGCCUUAAUUGGAGUCUAAACUCCACCUCCCUCUGUCUUUUCCUUUUCUUUUUCUUUCCUUCCUUCCUUUUCUUUUCUCCUUUAAAAAUAUUUUGAGCUUUGUGCUGAAGAAGUUUUUGGUGGGCUUUAGUGACUGUGCUUUGCAAAAGCAAUUAAGAACAAAGUUACUCCUUCUGGCUAUUGGGACCCUUUGGCCAGGAAAAAUUAUGCUUAGAAUCUAUUAUUUAAAGAAAUAUUUGUGAAAUGAAUUGGCAUCUUUAGGACUAAGUGUGCUCUGUUGAAUGACUUAAAGUGAGCUGUUCCUAAGCAGUGGAAGAAGAAGAAUCAUUCCUAUUCAUACAAAGUAAGAUUGGAGCAGUCAUACUGGGGAGAUUGUUUUGUGUGAACUAUAACGUGUAAGCAACUCCAUGAAAAGGCAUCUUGUUUACCUUUAUUCAGGGUGGAUCUCUUAGCCAUAUGUAUGAUCCUGUCUGAACCUGUCAACAGAGCAUGGAGCUAGUCUAUUUCACUAUAGAAAGAUUUUUAGACCUGGGGUUUAAGACAGUUUUUGGAACACCUAGUAAGAAUAUGGGACCUCACAUCUAGCACAGAAAUGCUCUUUGCCCUCUGGGUGGUAUGAUUAUAUGCCCAUGGAAUACAGCAUGGGAAAUGAUCACUUUUAGGAGGAUGAACUUGGAUUUUGAAUAUUUGAAACAUCUCUGAGUAAAAGAUUCGAUCAGAUAACUUGAAACAACAUGUAGUGGUUUUCUCAAUUAGAAGAUAACCAAGUGAAGGACCUGUCUUUUUCCUGUUCAUUUUACCUCAUUUUCUACUAUACAUUUAUCACCUUUCCUUUAUGUUUAAGGUUGUUAGAGGUUAUGAUAGUUUUAAAGAUGCAGUUAGGAAGGUAGAAUUCAAAGUGAAGCCUCCCCAGUCAGGAGCGAAGAUGUGCUUAUUUCCUUUUUUUUUUUUUUUUUUUUUUUUUGAGACAGAGUCUUGCUCUAUCACCCAGGCUGGAGUGCAGUGGCGCGAUCUCAGCUCACUGUAAGCUCCGCCUCCCGGGUUCAAGCAAUUCUCCUGCCUCAGCCUCCUGAGUAGCUGGGACUACAGGCAUGCGCCACUACGCCUGGCUAAUUUUUGUAUUUUUAGUAGAGACGGGGUUUCACCAUGUUGGCCAGGAUGGUCUUGAUCUCUUGACCUUGUGAUCCGCCCACCUCAGCCUCCCAAAGGCGCAGGCUCAGAUGUGCUUAUUUCUUUCAACUUUUUUUUUUUAAAUGGGGAAGAGCAGAGUUCAUUUGGGAAUGCUUAUACAUAGGGAUUGGAUUGUUCAUAUUAGUAGUAAAAAAUGUAGGCCUUAUUCUCUACAUUACCAAAUUUUUAAAAUAUUACUAUAUGGUAAUCAAUGCCAGGUACAGAUUUGUUGGUUCCCCAAACUGAAUUGAUAUCAGUAUCACAGUGGAGUCUUUUGAAAAUUAAAGUCCAGGAUUAAAUUAUAUGUUGUCACCAUUCACCACCACUACCACCCUCCCCCACCAAUCUCUCCCACCGGUUAAACUCGUCUUCUAAUCCUGUAGAAUCACAUGAACUAAAUGAAGAAGUAAGAACUUGAAGGCUCAGACUGACACUGUUACAAACUAGCAUCUUCAGAUGCAUGGUAUUUACUUUAAAUGUGCUUAUAUACAGUGUAGAGAAGCUCUUGUAUAAGAAGACAUCUAUGCUAGCUAACUUAGUAGUAGUAGAGGGAACAUAUUCAGUGAGCUGCCUUUAUAUCUGUAGUGUCGGAGACUUGUUACUGGUUCAUUUGUGGUUAUCAGUUGAAGGUUCUGUUCCUGAGAUGUGCAAUAGUAGUGUUGAAAGGUAUUGUUUAAUAGUGAUGGGGAACAGACAUAUUGGACUUUUUUUUCCAUAUUAAAUUAUUUAGUUUGCAUGCCUGUUUGAAAUUGGACCUCUCAGCAGCACUUUGAAAUAGUUUUAAUUAGGUUAACAUUUUGUACAUUAAAUAAGUAGAUAUAGAUGGUUGAUUUAACUAGAUGUGUUAAAUUUUGAAAGCACAAAGGUAUUUUAUCUUUUUGAAUUAAAGGAGAAAAGCCAUUGAUUUGUUUUCACAGACAGUAUUUUUAAUAAUUAACUGUCUCAGCACAGAGGUACCUUGGAACCAAGGGCACCAUUGAAACUCAGUUGAAGCAACUUCCUAGUAAACCAUUUUAGUGAGUCCUUUUUGCAUAAAUCUAUAGCCUCUCAGAGGUGUGAGGCUGUCACAGAUUGGUGAUCUGCUAUCUCUUUGAGAUCAACUAAUUUGGAGAAGUGUGUGUGUGCGUAUCCUUUUUUAAGUCAAAGUUUACAACCUUACUGCAGGUGUAUGAGGCAGACAGUUCUGUUUAUAGACUACCUCCUUCCUGGAAAAGUCUCAGCUUCAUAUUCUGUUGAAUAUAUGCAGAAUUCUUAGUGUGAAAGGUGAUGUACCACUUCAGAUCAGUUUUCACUGGAGAGACUUGUAAUUGGUAGCUGUAGCUCGUAUCCAUCCCUAGUCACUUUGCCAGGAUGAAUGCUGUUGGGCAGCAGUAGCCUAAGUUACGGAAGGGGAGCAGAUUGAAUGGGGUUUUGAGACAUCUUCUCUGAUACCUUAGCUUUCCUUCUGCUCUGGUCGCUAUCCACUCAGUCGUGUGCUAGAAAUGUUUAACAACCAGGAUCUCUGGGGUGGGGGUGGGGGGGAGCGCUGAAUUUGUAGCAUUUGCUGCAAAUAUAAAUUAUAAAUAAAAUUCUAAUAUAAAUUAGAAUUUUAUAUCAAAUUCUUUGAUAUAAAUUAGUUACUCCUCCUGUGGCUGAUUUCAAGCUACCACCUUAGAGUUCAGAAAGGAUGUGCACAGUUGGCUCAGAGCCAGUGCUGGCAAACCAUUGCAUUUACUCCACCCAAGAGUGGAUUUUCACAUAAUUUCUAAAAUAAUUUUUUCUUAUUUAUAUACUGACUUUUCAAAAUACAAAAUUAAAAUAUCAUGUCUGACUUCAGUGAUCUUUUUCUUUUUCUUUUUUUAGAAAUGAGAUCUUUCAGUAAUCCUUUAAUUUAAUUUUUUAGAGAUGGAGUCUUGGUGUGUUACCCAGGGUGGACUCAAACUCCCGGGCUCAAGUGAUCCUCCUGCCUCAGCCUCCUGCAUAGCUGGGCUACAGGCAUGCACCACCACACCUGGCUUAGUAAUCCUUCUUUAUUAAUGGUUUGUCACAGUACGUUUGUGAUGUUAUAUUGCUCAUGGCAUACUUUAUGUGUUCGAACAAAGGUGGAAAUUUCCAUUGAUUUUUUUUUUUUUAAAUGUAUGCACAAACAAUCUGGAUUUUGAGGAGUACGGUCAGGAAAAAAAAAAAAGAAUUAGAGGCCCUUGAAAGGUCAACCGUAAGCUUCUUAGAGUUAAAAUAUGAGUUUAAUUUUUUCCCACAUUUUGACAGUUGAAAUUUUGAUAGGGACAGUAAACCUAUGAGCCUCUAUUAGGCUACUGGAUUUUUUUUAACUGGAAAAUUCCUUGAAGAUUUACAUACUAUAUUACAGAUUUUAAAAGUCAAGACUGACUUAAGUAAAUCAGAGGUUUGGAAUUCUGGAGCUGUAACUCCAGGCUGUUGAUAGUAUCACUUCAGUUCCAUUCACCCCUGCAUUGUGUGACGUCCAGUCUGACAACAUUGUUUCAUCCUGAUCUGACUUUCUACUAUGAUUCUUAAGUUCUUAAAGGUGUCCUUUUAUGUUUUUGGUGAAUGUAAGCACAUUUAGAGCCACUCAGUACCACUUCUCAAUACCUCUGAAGCAGUGGUUCAGAAAAGGAGUGUCCAGCCUUUUUGAACACACAAAUUGAUCAGUAAGAGUUAUUGAACAUAAAAACUUUCCCUAUUAAAAAUUCAUAUGGGUAUAUGUUAAAUUAUAUACCGCUAUACCAAAGUAAUAUGUGUGUUAUAAAAAAAUACACAAAAAUUGAAGUGAAGGAUGGCAUAAAAAGUAAUUCUUGAGUAGCAGUUAUAGUAUUUUCUUCCCACACCCCAGUUGGUUGUCUUGUGCACCCUCCAGAAGCACACGCUUUUCCUAAAGACUGCUGACUCAGGAUAUUCUCAUUCUAAUCUCCAAACAUAUAUGAUGCUCUCUUAUGAUAUAUGGAGAAAUCCUAGAGAUUUGGAGUUUUUCAGGAGAGCUUAUUGUCAACUUUUGAAAUUUCACAUUAAUUCUUUUUGAUAAAUUCCCAAAUAAUAAUCCAUUACCACAUGUUUUCCACAGCUUUAUUCCUAUUACUUUCGUCAGCCUGUUGUCUCUUAUCUUCAUGUUAGGUAUGACUCUAUUUUUAUUUUACUAGUCUGCUCACAGACUUCUUUGGGACUUAUGUUAUAUUUUACCAACAAAUUUAGAAUUAUUUCAAGUUGCUUUAUGUUAAAAUAUAUAACAAGUUACAUUUUCUUGCUGCAUUAAUAAGUUUUUGAUUUUUAAAAUCUGAUAUUUCAGCAACUAAAGGAAUACUUUUCUUUAUAGGUCUGUUCUGUUUUUAACCUCAUUGACUGUAUAUGUUUUAUUUACCCGUGCCAGGAGUCUAGAAUCGUGCUUAGGUGCCAUUCUUAGGUAUGAAAACAAGUUUGGAGACCAAUGCAGGUCUCUGUGCAGAAAUCUGGGGCUCUAAAUGAAUUACCAAACCAAUAGGAAAGUUAAAAUACUACUCAUGAUGUAGUGUGUCAUCUGAAGCUAUGAUAGAAUAUAUUAUUUCUAAAAUAGUAUUGAGAAGUUAAUUGUUCAGUCCAUAGUAGUGUAAGUGAAGUGUGGAGGUCAGCCAUAGUUGUCUUUCUUCAGCAGGUACUCUAACCAGAGACUGGGUUCUGUGGAAAAUAGAAUUAUAUUCUUGGUUUGGGAUCAACAAAUGUUUUGUUAUUGUUUUAAUGUUGCUGGCAUUGCCUGAAACAAAGUGCCCUGUUAUUCCUCUUAUGUCAUCAGAACUCUGCUUACUGAAGUUGAAGUUUAAUCUUAGGAUCUAGAAUUCUUGUGGUUGGUCGUGUAUUAAGAAAAGAAGGUGGUUUGAUUUUAUUUCUUGUACUUGGUGGAACCUGUUACUAUACAAGUCAUGUUUUGACCUGUAAGCCGAGCAAAUCUGAAAGGUGAAUCGUUAAUGGUAGUAUAAUUGUUUCAUUUGAAACUGUCAGUUUCUUCAAGUCACUUCUCUGAAAAAAAUUAUGAUAGAUUGAUAGCCUGCCAGAAAAUAGCAAUUUCUAAGGUGCUGCCAUCCACACUUACUUAUUGUGAAAUAUGAAAAUCCAGAGUGGUUUGUAUGAGAGGGGAAAUACUGGCUCUAAGCUUUCUACAGAAAACAGGAAAUUCAUGCUGUUGUUGACAUAAUUUUAAAGGAAACUUUUAACAAGAAAAUUCAUGAGGGAUACAAUCAAACAUAGUUAAUCUCUUGAGUGCUAAUCAUUUGAGUAUAGUCCACAUCAGGAAGUUUUAUGAGGUUGAAAACUUUACUUUGAAAUAUUUAAUUGGGAGACUAGACCAUUUCUUUUUCCAAGUCAUUCUGAUUUAUUGUCCUAGUAAAUGUAUGUGUAUGCAUAUAUACUGAUGUAUUGACUGAAUGUGUGUGUGUGUGUGUGUGCGCGUGUAAAUCUGUUUUCAUAGGGAACAUACAUUGAUGGCUCCUAGUCUAUUUUAUACUAAAACUUAAAAAAAUUUGCUGCACUUUGCAGUUGCCACUUUUUAAAAGAUUAAUGCUUUGCACAUUUCAGUAGGCCUUAAAGAUGAAUUGCUCACCAACAUUUUAGAAAUACACUGCUUACAUGUGACAUACUCUAAACAAAGUCAUAGUAAACUGUUCUCUUAGGUUCAUGUAUUAUUGAGCAAAUAAGGAUGUCCUUUCUUAAAAUUUCUACAUUUAUGUUUGCUUUUGUGUAAAAUCUUUAUUAGUUUGUAAGUUUCUCAAAGAGGAGGUUUAUACUGGAAGCAGUAUUUCUAAAGUACAGAGAUUCGACCAUGGAUUGAAUACAGUAGUGGAGGAAUGCUGGUAUUGUGGCCUAAUUUAUCCUUUUAAACUGUAUGUCAUUAGUAUUAGCCAAAACCUCAGAGUGGAGUGUCUUGGGCUGAAUGAUCUUCUCAACUUUGCCUUGUUUCCCAUCUCAUAAAGGCUCCUUCUGGUUCUUUUCCCUUCCAAGGAUUGUGAGUCAUGCUCACAUAGGCCUGGGAUCUUCUGGAUGGGGUCGGGGAGGAGGUGGGGGUUUCCUGUGGCUGGCCCAGAGUUCUAGCCAAUGGAAUCAUUCAAGAAUGCCUAAAGUUCAGGGGUGGGAAUGCCAUAUAUUGGUGUUAAUCACUUGGCACUUUCUUGGGCACCAAUAUUAGCACUGUUUCAUUUUUAAUAACUGGAAGCACUUAAUGAUUAUUUUGUUUGUUUAAUUUCAACUUAAGGAUAUUGAGGGUCAGAGAAGUAAGGUUUAUUUCUUGUUUAUGUUUUCUGGAAUUUAUAGGGUGUUUGUAGAAGGGAUAAAUGGGUUACCUAAUGAGCCAUUCUUCUAGGCUCUGUAAGGUAUGCCCUUUUGGCUAGGAUAUUUUAAAAUAAUUUGCAAGCUUUUAAUAUUGUGCUUUGUAGAAAUUUACGAUUUUUAAAAAUAAUUUGCAAUUGAUAGAUUACACUUAAAUUUAUAAAGUAUCCAAUUUUAAGUUUCUUUUCUGUUUGGUCAUUGUUGCUUAUUGUCUAUUGUGUAGGGGACACAAUCCUGACAUUUCAUUGUUUUGUUACUUGGGGCAGUAUUAACCAGUGGCCUUUGUAUGUACAUUCAUUGCUUACAUUUAUUGUUUAAGUGGUAGAGUAGCAUUUUUAUGAACUUCCCUGUUCAGUAUUAGUGAAAUUGACAGAUGCGUAUAUGUAAAGAUAGAAAAGAAACGAAUACAAUUAAUUUUUUAUUCCUUGAGGCCUAUUUAUUUGUUUUGGCCCUGGAUCUUUUCUAAUCACAAUUAUAUUUCUUUAUUUUUGCCUUUGAGCAGUUUCAUUUAUCUUUGUGGGCAGGGAAGAUUAAAUAUGAAAUUCAGUCCAGUCAUUUUGCUACUGGUUAGCUUUAGUUUGAGGCAAGUAAAAAUUUUUGAUUAAAAUUAGUUUCUUAAAAUUAUGCCCUUGCUUUACCAAAUAAUCAAAUUGGCUAAAAAAUAAGGGUAUGUAACUUUGCAUUUUGAAGAACAAACCAAUAAUUUUUCAUGAGCCCUACUCGAUCUUCUUUAAAGAAGACCUUCCUAAGAGACAAUUAGGGAUGAGUUUGAUUAAUGGGAAAUAGCUCUAGGUUAGAUUAUUUUAAAUUCCAUACACCAAGUGAUUUAACCACAGUGGCAGUGGCAGUUUCUGAACCGUCAAGUAUGAACAUCACUUAAAAAUUAAAAGAUGCUUAAUAAUAAACUCUUAAUUUUCAUUAAGCCAAUCUGUAAUUCAGAAGAAAAGCAUAUGUCUGCCAUGGGACUAUUGCAGUGCGUCUCCAUCAGUGUUAACACAGGAGAGAUAUGUUAUUUUAUGUGUAUGUCUUAGUUUGGGAUAUGUGGUAGUAAGAACAUGUCAAGAGUGCUUUCUUCAAACCUGUCAGCUCAACUGAGAAGACAGUUACUUCAUUGCUUAUUUUUUCCCUUGUUUUAUUGAAAUCUGUAUCUCAUAUCCAGUAUCUAACACUUUGUAGAGAUACUUACAUAUAAUGUAAGUGCACACCUACCCAGAGGAAUGGAUAACUGUUAAAGUGUUAAUAAUAGCUCGUCUUAGUUGAUUUCAGCAUAAUUUACAUUAGGGAGACCUAAAAAGCACCUUCAAAGUAUUAAAAGCACCUUUUUUUUUUCUUUUUCCUAAAAAAGCAAUUAAAAUGGUCACUGCUAACAUUUAUUAAACUUCAUGUUAGUUGAUGAAACAGCUGGAGGGAAGCUGCCACAUCUCCUAGCUAAGCAGUCUGACUUACCUGUUGGGAAACAAAGGGAUAUUGCUCUAAGAUUGAUUAGGAUGAUUGUAGCUAGAGUCUUGAAUUCUAUCUGUAUACGGCAGAGAAACUUUAUAGAGUGUAGAGAGGUGAGCGAAAGGAUGCAAAAGCACUUUGAGGGCUUUAUAAUAAUAUGCUGCUUGAAAAAAAAAAUGUGUAGUUGAUACUCAGUGCAUCUCCAGACAUAGUAAGGGGUUGCUCUGACCAAUCAGGUGAUCAUUUUUUCUAUCACUUCCCAGGUUUUAUGCAAAAAUUUUGUUAAAUUCUAUAAUGGUGAUAUGCAUCUUUUAGGAAAGAUAUACAUUUUUAAAAAUCUAUUUUAUGUAAGAACUGACAGAGGAAUUUGCUUUGUAUAAUGCAGGCUGGCUUUACAAAAGCACUGUAGCAAAUUUACUACAAGUCUAAAAGUAUACAUAUAUGUUAAUAGAUAUAUGUGCAACUAGAUAUGGACAGCAGUUGUAUUUUUUUAAAUAAAUAUUUUUAACAAAAUGA